AAGCCGCGAGGAGCGCGGACGGCUGGGCUGCUGCUGGGCGGCCGCGGGGCAGCGGAGGGCGCCGGCACUCCGGUCCCCGCCGCUCCCCGUCCCCGCUGCUCCUAGCCCCUGCCGCGUCCCCGGCGGAGCGGGCAUGGCGCCACCCGCGGCGCCUGGCCGGGACCGUGUGGGCCGUGAGGAUGAGGACGGCUGGGAGACGCGAGGGGACCGCAAGGCCCGGAAGCCCCUGGUGGAGAAGAAGCGGCGCGCGCGGAUCAACGAGAGCCUGCAGGAGCUGCGGCUGCUGCUGGCGGGCGCCGAGGUGCAGGCCAAGCUGGAGAACGCCGAAGUGCUGGAGCUGACGGUGCGGCGGGUCCAGGGUGUGCUGCGGGGCCGGGCGCGCGAGCGCGAGCAGCUGCAGGCGGAAGCGAGCGAGCGCUUCGCUGCCGGCUACAUCCAGUGCAUGCACGAGGUGCACACGUUCGUGUCCACGUGCCAGGCCAUCGACGCUACCGUCGCUGCCGAGCUCCUGAACCAUCUGCUCGAGUCCAUGCCGCUGCGUGAGGGCAGCAGCUUCCAGGAUCUGCUGGGGGACGCCCUGGCGGGGCCACCUAGAGCCCCUGGACGGAGUGGCUGGCCUGCGGGGGGCGCUCCGGGAUCCCCAAUACCCAGCCCCCCGGGUCCUGGGGACGACCUGUGCUCCGACCUGGAGGAGGCCCCUGAGGCUGAACUGAGUCAGGCUCCUGCUGAGGGGCCCGACUUGGUGCCCGCAGCCCUGGGCAGCCUGACCACAGCCCAAAUUGCCCGGAGUGUCUGGAGGCCUUGGUGACCAAUGCCAGCCAGAGUCCUGCGGGGGUGGGCCCGGCCCUCCCUGGAUCUCCUCCCUCCUCCCAGGGGUUCAGAUGUGGUGGGGUAGGGCCCUGGAAGUCUCCCAGGUCUUCCCUCCCUCCUCUGAUGGAUGGCUUGCAGGGCAGCCCCUGGUAACCAGCCCAGUCAGGCCCCAGCCCCGUUUCUUAAGAAACUUUUAGGGACCCUGCAGCUCUGGAGUGGGUGGAGGGAGGGAGCUACGGGCAGGAGGAAGAAUUUUGUAGAGCUGCCAGCGCUCUCCCAGGUUCACCCACCCAGGCUUCACCAGCCCUGUGCGGGCUCUGGGGGCAGAGGUGGCAGAAAUGGUGCUGGGCACUAGUGUUCCAGGCAGCCCUGGGCUAAACAAAAGCUUGAACUUGCCACUUCAGCGGGGAGAUGAGAGGCAGGUGCACUGAGCUGCACUGCCCAGAGCUGUGAUGCUCUGUACAUCUUGUUUGUAGCACACUUGAGUUUGUGUAUUCCAUUGACAUCAAAUGUGACAAUUUUACUAAAUAAAGAAUUUUGGAGUUAGUUACCCUUGAA